CAUUUACUUGGCACACAGUAGGUUCUCAGAAGGUGUCAGUUUCUGUGUUUUUCUCACAGAAUCCCUGUAAACUCAAGAGAGUAAAAAUGAAGAUUGUGUAGUAGUCAUUGCUGAUUAUAAACCACUUCAGAACUCAUUGGCUUAGAGCCAUAAGGGUUUACAAUUGCUAACGAGUCUGUGAGACAGCUGGCCAGUUCUUCUGGAUGUGGAAGGGAUCACUCUUGGCACAUGAGCAGCUGUGGGUCGGGGGGCAGCUUUGCUGAUCCUGGCUCAGUUCAUUCACGUUUGGGGCUUCAGUACCUUCAGACUCAUCUGGGAUGGGCUCAGCUGUGACACCUGGACUUUCCCCCAUGUGAUUCUCUGCCUCCAGAAGGCACCCUGUUGUUCACAUGGCAGAGACUGGGCUCCGAGAAACUGAGAGGAGGCUGCAAUGUCUGUGGACAUUGUCUCUGCAAUACUUCAAAGUUCAACCAGGUUUGAGUCUAUUAGAGUUAUUACAUCAUCAUUUCACCACAUUGUACUGGCCAAAGAAAGUCGAAAGUCAAAAGUCCAGUACAGACUCAAAGGGGUGUAAAAUAGAACGCAUCUCUUAAUGGGAGUUGCUGAAAAAUUACUGUGGAAAGGGUACGAAUACAGGGAGAAGUGAAGAAUUGGGGGUCAGGAUUUUGUGAAGUGUCUAGGAUUUGUUUUAAAUAUGCAAACUGAUAAGUUAGCUUGUUACUGUCUCAUGCAUUCUAACAGAUUCCUGGGUCAGAGACAAAGGGUAGUUGAUUACUCAUGGCACAAUAAGCAACAUGUACUUCUUGUUGGUUUGUAUCCUUUUUCUGAGUCAACCUAAAUUCCAUGGGGGUGACACUGGUGGGCCUCUACAUUAGCCUGCUCAUGCAGUACAUUGCAUGACAUACAAUGGGCAUUAGGCUUAGGGAAUCUACUUUAAUAGUGGCAGAAACAAGCCUGAUAUUGGUCCAGGAGGAGUCAUUGCCUUAUCUCUCCAGGUGGUUAUCUGCAAAUACAACUCUGAGAAAUGGCUCAGGUAAGAACAUCACAGUCUUGCAUUGGUGGCAUACGCAGCAAGGAUGCUCAGGGCUGAUGAAGAAGUGCCUCUUCCAACACAGGGAUAUUUUUGAAAUGAAUUUAUUACAAUGGAGAUGAAUAAAGCAAACAUUUACUCAUCAUAUGCCUGAGAAAAUGUCAUGUCCCAAUGCCAGGAUAUAAGUUGUCUAAGUUAAUUUUAAUAAUCCUGUGAGGUUAUGGUUAUUUUUGUCCUAUUGCAGAUGAUGAACUGAGGGCCAGAGAGAUUAGGGAGCUGGACAGAGUUCAACCAGCCAGGAAGUGAGCUAGGACUGGUGGAGCAGAGAUUCUAUCCUGGUUUAUCUGGCCCCAAAGCAGAUCACCUUGACCGUUAUUGAAUAUUUGACAGGACAAGUGGCAGCACCUGGCCUCAGAGGGCAGCAGUCGUCUGGACAUGUUUGAGCACAUCAGCCUCAUGACCUUGGACAGUCUACAGAAAUGCAUCUUCAGCUUUGACAGCCAUUGUCAGGAGAGGCCCAGUGAAUAUAUUGCCACCAUCUUGGAGCUCAGUGCCCUUGUAGAGAAAAGAAGCCAGCAUAUCCUCCAGCACAUGGACUUUCUGUAUUACCUCUCCCAUGACGGGCGGCGCUUCCACAGGGCCUGCCGCCUGGUGCAUGACUUCACAGACGCUGUCAUCCGGGAGCGGCGUCGCACCCUCCCCACUCAGGGUAUUGAUGAUUUUUUCAAAGACAAAGCCAAGUCCAAGACUUUGGAUUUCAUUGAUGUGCUUCUGCUGAGCAAGGAUGAAGAUGGGAAGGCAUUGUCAGAUGAGGAUAUAAGAGCAGAGGCUGACACCUUCAUGUUUGGAGGCCAUGACACCACGGCCAGUGGCCUCUCCUGGGUCCUGUACAACCUUGCGAGGCACCCAGAAUACCAGGAGCGCUGCCGACAGGAGGUGCAAGAGCUUCUGAAGGACCGCGAUCCUAAAGAGAUUGAAUGGGACGACCUGGCCCAGCUGCCCUUCCUGACCAUGUGCGUGAAGGAGAGCCUGAGGUUACAUCCCCCAGCUCCCUUCAUCUCCCGAUGCUGCACCCAGGACAUUGUUCUCCCAGAUGGCCGAGUCAUCCCCAAAGGCAUUACCUGCCUCAUCGAUAUUAUAGGGGUCCAUCACAACCCAACUGUGUGGCCGGAUCCUGAGGUCUACGACCCCUUCCGCUUUGACCCAGAGAACAGCAAGGGGAGGUCACCUCUGGCUUUUAUUCCUUUCUCCGCAGGGCCCAGGAACUGCAUCGGGCAGGCGUUCGCCAUGGCGGAGAUGAAAGUGGUCCUGGCGUUGAUGCUGCUGCACUUCCGGUUCCUGCCAGACCACACUGAGCCCCGCAGGAAGCUGGAAUUGAUCAUGCGCGCCGAGGGCGGGCUUUGGCUGCGGGUGGAGCCCCUGAAUGUAAGCUUGCAGUGACUUUCUGACCCAUCCACCUGUUUUUUUGCAGAUUGUCAUGAAUAAAACGGUGCUGUCACCUCUGCCUGGGCCUCACUGACAGCCUGCAG